AAGUGCAGCUGCUUCAGGCUGAGGUGGCAGAUAGUGAGCGCUGGUGGCGGAGUUAAAGUCAAAGCAGGAGAGUAAUUAUGAAUAGCGCAGCGGGAUUCUCACACCUAGACCGUCGCGAGCGGGUUCUCAAGUUAGGGGAGAGUUUCGAGAAGCAGCCGCGCUGCGCCUUCCACACUGUGCGCUAAUUGUAGAGCGGGAAGGAAACUUCAAGAUCACUGAAUUAUAACUUCUCAUUUUUCUGUGGUAAAACUAGCUCCCCACGAUGAGAUGGUGCUGUGCUGGCUCUGCAGUUUCUCUCUCUUCAGUCCCAUUUUCCGGAAGUGUGAUAUGCGUCUUUAUCUGGUUUUUCCAUGCCUUUUUCUCAAAUAGUAUCUACUCUCUCCUUUUCUCUUCCUUCUCAGAUGACUUCAAACCUGCUUCUAUUGACACUUCUUCUGAAGGAUACCUUGAGGUUGGUGAAGGUGAACAGGUGACCAUAACUCUGCCAAAUAUAGAAGGUUCAACUCCACCAGUAACUGUUUUCAAAGGUUCAAAAAAACCUUACUUAAAAGAAUGCAUUUUGAUUAUUAACCAUGAUACUGGAGAAUGUCGGCUAGAAAAACUCAGCAGCAACAUCACUGUAAAAAAAACAAGAGUUGAAGGAAGCAGUAAAAUUCAGUAUCGUAAAGAACAACAGCAACAACAAAUGUGGAAUUCAGCCAGGACUCCCAAUCUUGUAAAACAUUCUCCAUCUGAAGAUAAGAUGUCCCCAGCAUCUCCAAUAGAUGAUAUCGAAAGAGAACUGAAGGCAGAAGCUAGUCUAAUGGACCAGAUGAGUAGUUGUGAUAGUUCAUCAGAUUCCAAAAGUUCAUCAUCUUCAAGUAGUGAGGAUAGUUCUAGUGACUCAGAAGAUGAAGAUUGCAAAUCCUCUACUUCUGAUACAGGGAAUUGUGUCUCAGGACAUCCUACCAUGACACAGUACAGGAUUCCUGAUAUAGAUGCCAGUCAUAAUAGAUUUCGAGACAACAGUGGCCUUCUGAUGAAUACUUUAAGAAAUGAUUUGCAGCUGAGUGAAUCAGGAAGUGACAGUGAUGACUGAAGAAAUAUUUAGCUAUAAAUAAAAAUUUAUACAGCAUGUAUAAUUUAUUUUGUAUUAACAAUAAAAAUUCCUAAGACUGAGGGAAAUAUGUCUUAACUUUUGAUGAUAAAAGAAAUUAAAUUUGAUUCAGAAAUUUCA